AAACCGGAAUGGCCCGAGGGAAGGCCGCGCAGGGCAGGGCCCCAGAUGGUUCCUGUCAGGGAAGUGGCGGGCGCAGCUGCAGGCCUCCGGCCCCGGCAUUAUCACGGGGACACAGCUGGCUGCCUCACCCGCAGGCUGCAGGGAGACCUUCCCCAGCCUGCAGCCCCAGGCCCGCCCCGCGUCACAUGAGCCCCAGGGCUCCCACCCCCUCCCCAGGGCAGAGGACACCCAGUUGGUGGCCGGGAGGGCCUCGGCUUUCCAGGGACAGAGGCCCAACUCCAGGACGCCCCAGCUGGCCCAGCCCCUCCUCUUUCCCUCAAGGCUGCAGGAGGUCGGGAAAGGCAGUCCUGGUAGAGGCCUGUCCUGGGCUCCAGGUUGGCCCCUGAGGGUGGCCCUCCUCAUGCCGGCUUCAAGACUGAGGGACAGGGCAGCCAGUUCAGCCUCGGGAUCCACCUGUGGCUCCAUGUCCCAGACGCACCCUGUGCUGGAGAGCGGCCUCCUGGCAUCUGCCGGCUGCUCCGCACCCCGGGGUCCCAGGAAGGGCGGCCCAGCCCCAGUGGACAGGAAAGCUAAGGCCUCAGCGAUGCCGGACUCCCCAGCGGAGGUGAAGACGCAGCCCCGGUCCACACCCCCCAGCAUGCCGCCCCCACCGCCUGCCGCAUCCCAGGGGGCCACACGCCCCCCCUCCUUCACGCCACACACACUGAUGAACGGCAGCAGCCACUCACCAACAGCCAUCAAUGGUGCACCGUGCACACCCAACGGCUUCAGCAAUGGCCCGGCCACCUCGUCCACAGCCUCCUUGUCCACACAGCACCUGCCCCCAGCCUGCGGGGCCCGGCAGCUCAGCAAGCUCAAGCGCUUCCUCACCACACUGCAGCAGUUUGGCAGCGACAUCUCCCCAGAGAUUGGGGAGCGCGUGCGCACACUGGUGCUGGGCCUGGUGAACUCGACAUUGACGAUCGAGGAGUUUCAUUCCAAGCUUCAGGAGGCCACCAACUUCCCUCUGCGGCCGUUUGUCAUUCCCUUCCUGAAGGCAAACCUGCCCUUGCUGCAGCGGGAGCUCCUGCACUGUGCACGCCUGGCCAAGCAGACGCCCGCCCAGUACUUGGCCCAGCAUGAGCAGCUCCUGCUGGACGCCAGCGCCUCCUCCCCCAUCGACUCCUCAGAGCUGCUACUGGAAGUCAACGAGAACGGCAAGAGGAGGACGCCCGACAGGACCAAAGAGAACGGGUCAGACCGCGACCCGCUGCACCCCGAGCACCUCAGCAAACGGCCAUGCACCCUGAACCCUGCCCAGCGCUACAGCCCCAGCAACGGGCCACCGCAGCCCACACCGCCGCCGCACUACCGCCUGGAGGACAUAGCCAUGGCCCACCACUUCCGAGAUGCCUACCGCCACCCAGACCCCCGGGAGCUACGAGAGCGCCAUCGGCCGCUUGUGGUGCCUGGGUCCCGGCAGGAAGAAGUGAUCGACCACAAGCUCACAGAGCGUGAGUGGGCAGAAGAGUGGAAGCACCUCAACAACCUCCUGAACUGCAUCAUGGACAUGGUGGAGAAGACGCGGCGCUCGCUCACGGUGCUGCGCAGGUGCCAGGAGGCCGACCGCGAGGAGCUCAACCACUGGGCGCGGCGCUACAGCGACGCCGAGGACACAAAGAAGGGCCCCGCUCCCGCCGCGGCCCGGCCCCGCAGCAGCUCCGCCGGUCCCGAAGGGCCUCAGCUAGACGUGCCUCGCGAGUUCCUGCCGAGGACCCUCACCGGCUACGUGCCUGAGGACAUCUGGAGGAAGGCUGAAGAGGCCGUGAAUGAGGUGAAGCGGCAGGCCAUGUCGGAGCUGCAGAAAGCCGUGUCGGACGCGGAGCGCAAAGCGCACGAGCUCAUCACCACGGAGCGUGCCAAGAUGGAGCGGGCCCUGGCCGAGGCGAAGCGGCAGGCCUCCGAGGACGCCCUGACGGUCAUCAACCAGCAGGAGGACUCCAGCGAGCUAGGGAGAAGCUAGACCACCACAGGCACAACUCUCACAGAGCUGGCACUGAGAAGGAAACACCAAACGCAGAAGUGAGGCGUGCAGUUUCGGGAGGUGGAAGUGUGUGGGGAGUGGGGCUGUGGAGGCCUCACGGCAGGUGACACCUGAGCAGAUGCCGGGAGGAAUGAAGCUGGCCACGCAGGCAUCGGGGGAGCGGGCCCAGCGGAGGGACCGGCAGGGGCCAGGGCCUGGAGCGGGGACUGUGCCUGGCAGUGCCUAGUCCGCAGGGAAGCUGCUGCUGCAGUGGCAGUGAGGGCGAGGUGGGGUGGGAGGUGGUACCAGAGGCUUUGGAGGCCAAAUAGGGACCUGGGCUUCUCCCCUAGGGCAGGUUUGGGCUUCCCACCCCACAGCCCAACCGUCUGUGAGAGAUCCAGCCAGGCCCCAAGAAGAAAUAUGCUCAGGCUUUGUGUGGCAUCUCCUACCUGCUCUGCCCACAGGCUUUUUGUGGCAUCCCCCACCCCCUCUGCCCACAGGGAUGCCUAGGGCACAACUCACCCUACGGGAAGGGAGCAGAGCCCACCACAGGGUGGGGGCAGAGGUGGAGGGGGUGCAGCAGAGGCAGGGGUGGGGCAGAGGUGGGGAGGGGGACGGGUGGGUGUGGAUGCAGCAGAGGCGGAUGGUGAGAUCUCAGCAGCCUCAAUCCUGCCGGGGCCACGCCCUUUGGUUUUGCGGUUUUGGAGCCUGGUGAGCUCAGGAGGGCUUCCUGGAGAGGAGGCAGGGGUCGUUGUCCAGUUAGCACAGCGCAGACCUAUCUGGGUGGGCUGGAGCGUGAGACACGGUAGUGGGAUGCCGUCCCGCAAAAUGGCCCAGUGAGUGGCUGUAUCUGGAGCAUGGCCCGAGGGCUGUGGGGCUUUGGAGUUUCUCUCUUCUCACCUGGUGAUGACGUGGCUGGGUCUGAAUGGCUUGGUUGAGGCGUGUGUUGGGGAUUCGGGUGGCCAGACCCAGCCCUGACUGGCCCCUCUGCCCCCACCCAGAGCUGCUGGAACUGCGGGCGGAAAGCCAGUGAGACGUGCAGCGGCUGCAACGCGGCACGCUACUGCGGGUCCUUCUGCCAGCAUCGGGACUGGGAGAAGCAUCACCACGUGUGUGGCCAGAGCCUGCAGGGCCCCACAGCCGUGGUGGCCGACCCGGUGCCUGGACCGCCCGAAGCCGCCCACAGCCUGGGCCCCUCCCUGCCUGUGGGUGCUGCCAGCCCCAGCGAAGCCGGCUCUGCGGGGCCUUCUCGCCCCGGCUCCCCCAGCCCACCUGGCCCACUGGACACCGUGCCCCGCUGACCCCACUGGCCCCUGGCCUGCCGGACACAGCACCGUGCCAACCCCACCCAGCUCCAGGCCCACCGGAUGCUGUGCCUGGCCUCCGAUGCCUGGCCUGCCAGACACUGCGCCCCGCCUGACCUGGGGGAGCCGACCAAUUAGUCACUGCUGCUACUGCCCCUCUCCGAAAGAAGACACAGAACCAACAAAACCGCAUUCAGUGCACCUGCCUCAGCUACCUAAUGAUUCCGCGCGGAGACCUCCUGACAACGUCUCUUCAAGCAUCCUCAGAAGCCUCGACUGAGCUUUAGACAGCAGAGCAGAUGCCGCAGGCGCGGCGGCUCUGCCCACCUCUCUUUUCCUCUCUGUCUGUCUCUCCCCCUCUGUCUUCUCUAUCCUCUCUCUCUCUAUGACUAUCACACACUUUCUCUUCAAUGAAAAAAUCGAAUUGGUGGCUUAUAUUUUCAGCAAAGAAUUUUGGGGGGUUUUGUGUGUUGGCAAAAGAGCUACUCAGAAAUGGACAAAGAAAACGGGGGGGUUCUCCCCCUCCUGAUUAAAAAGGGAGAAAGAAAACUGCGAUUUUAUAGCUGGAGAUCUGAACCCAGCUGUGCCCCUCCCCCAGGGGCGUGAGGCUGAUCAGCGAAGACGGGAGGAAAGAUUUCGAUUUCUGACUCAAGAUGCAUUUUUGGUUUCAGAUUUUUUUUUCCUGUAAUGUUAAACUCUUUGGCUUUAAGUAAAAAUCCAAAAAGUUUUUUUAAAAAAGCAAAGGAAGCAUACUUGUGAACUACCUUGCUAGCUAGCCAGCCAAGGAUACCGGACACACCUCUGCUCCAAAGGAAAUCCAAAAAAGCAAACACAAGAAAUCAAAAUCCAAAAUUUGUUUGUCACUGCCAAAGUAUUUUUUUCACUGUUUCACUUGCUCUUGGGUUUGUUUGGAUGUGGGUCUUUUUCUCUUCUGUUCUGAUUUUGUUUGUGGGUGUCGGGAUAUUUGGGUGCAGAGGGUUUGUGCCCAGUUAGAAGCGACUUUUGUUCUCUUCUGCGUAGGCGUUGGUGCGUCCGCCGCGUGUGCGUGGUCCGUGUGCCGUUGCUCCGGCCUGCGUCUCCAUAUGUGUAGGAAAGGACACGCCGUCUGUCCUCACGCCCCCUGUGACUUUUCAUAUUUCCGUUUUCCACUUGUGGAAAAAAAGUGCUAAAGUUUUCUUCCCAGAGAGAGCAUAAUUCCGAAACAAAACUGUGACAAUCUUUUGGGUUGAUUCUCGACUGCUUUUCGAGCAUGCGGAGCCAGCAGGCCUCCCUGAAACACUGCUUCUCGGCCAGCCCGUCCUCCUCUACCUCUCUCCUCUCCGCGCCCUCCGACCUCUCUCGGCCCCCUCACCCCAGCUCCGACCUCUCUCAGCCCCAUCGCCCCAACUCCAACCUCUCGGCCCCAUCGCCCCACCGCAGCUACUCCCCUUUCUUCCAAACUUUUGCAGAAAAAACAAAAAAACUACAAACAAAAGCAGCCCUCUGCCUCCUCCCCAGGGAAGACCCUGACCGUGUACAUAGCCCUGGUGCUCCUGCCCAGCCACCCCUCAGAUGCGUUCGCCUCUGGCCCUGGGGUGUGUCUCGGUGACGUUUUCUAUCAGACGUGCUCCCUCCCAUCCUCCAGCCCUGCCCACCCUCCCUCCACUCCUCUCAACUGCCUCAGCGAUUUCAAGAAGGAAAUAAAGGGAUAAAGAAAUUCAUGCUUGCACCGAGUACAAGGACAGACAGCAGGCACGGCCCGCAGCCUGGCAUCUGUGCGUGUGGCGUGGCCCGUGGCUUGGCAUCUGUGUGCGUGGUGUGGCCCGUGGCCUGGCAUCUGUGUGCGUGGCGUGGCCCGUGGCCUGGCAUCUGUGUGUGUGGCGUGGCCCGUGGCCUGGCAUCUGUGCGCGUGGCGUGGCCCGUGGCCUGGCAUCUGUGUGCGUGGCUAUCAGGAGUUCUAGGAACUCAGUGCAAUACGGGAGUGACCCAGCUACUGAACCAGCCACGAACAGCCCGCCAGAGGCCUGAAGCUGAGCGUGUACGUUAAUGUGAAUGUAUAUAGUCUUUGCAGAGGUCCAAAUGAUAUUCAUGAUGGUAAUAAACGAGAUGUUUGCCAAAUAAAAAACAGAAACCGCA